ACCAGAGCCAAUUUGUCCUCUAUAUGAACCAGGUUAGGCAUAAUCCUUCUCAGAAGCAAGGGAGUAGACAAAAUGAUUCUCUUCUUUCUUGCCCCUCAGAGAGACCUGAGACACCCUGAAUCCCACUGUAAUCUCCUUGGUGCCAUUGGUAACUCUGCCAAAGUCCAUCUCUAGGUGACAUGAAGUCUCUUAGAAAUUGAGGACCAAAUUGCGCUCUGCAGCUCUGGGCUACUUCCCAUCUCAUUUUGUGUCCCUAUUUUCGUAUCUGUAUUAGAGAGGUAAUUACCAUAUCAUUGAAGAUCUCCAUAUAUGUGUCUAUGAGUUAAUAUUUAAGACCAACCUUUCUUAUUAUCAGAUGUCAUCCUCUGUGUUUUUCCCAGUGCCCUCACUCCCAAACCCUUUGUUCCUUCUCUUCUCAUUGCACCUGCAUCAGCUGUGGGCAUCCUUCCCAUUCUACCAUUAGACACCAGAGGAAACAGCAAGACCUAGAAUACCUAGGUUCUAACUCACAUUGUCUGGGCAGUUUGUUUGGUCAAUCUCCUAGGAUACAGAGAAAAGUGAGGCUGAGCAGAGGGACACGCAUGCUACUGAGUUCUGAACCCAAGUGUCCUCCCUUCUGGACCACAGUCUCAAAAUUCUCAAAGGAGAUGAGACUCAGAGCCAUUGCGAAUUAGUGGAGUCAAAAGAGGGAACCAACUGGAAGAGGUGAUGGGGAGAAGGGAUGAGGAGAAGGAAGAGAAGAGGAGAGACUGACCUAGGUGAUCUGGUGCCAGCUGGUGGAACAGUGGGUGAUGGCGUCCCUGCUGCAAGACCAGCUGACCACUGAUCAGGACUUGCUGCUGAUGCAGGAAGGCAUGCCGAUGCGCAAGGUGAGGUCCAAAAGCUGGAAGAAGCUAAGAUACUUCAGACUUCAGAAUGACGGCAUGACAGUCUGGCAUGCACGGCAGGCCAGGGGCAGUGCCAAGCCCAGCUUCUCAAUCUCUGAUGUGGAGACAAUACGUAAUGGCCAUGAUUCCGAGUUGCUGCGUAGCCUGGCAGAGGAGCUCCCCCUGGAGCAGGGCUUCACCAUUGUCUUCCAUGGCCGCCGCUCCAACCUGGACCUGAUGGCCAACAGUGUUGAGGAGGCCCAGAUAUGGAUGCGAGGGCUCCAGCUGUUGGUGGAUCUUGUCACCAGCAUGGACCAUCAGGAGCGCCUGGACCAAUGGCUGAGCGAUUGGUUUCAACGUGGAGACAAAAAUCAGGAUGGUAAGAUGAGUUUCCAAGAAGUUCAGCGGUUAUUGCACCUAAUGAAUGUGGAAAUGGACCAAGAAUAUGCCUUCAGUCUUUUUCAGGCAGCAGACACGUCCCAGUCUGGAACCCUGGAAGGAGAAGAAUUCGUACAGUUCUAUAAGGCAUUGACUAAACGUGCUGAGGUGCAGGAACUGUUUGAAAGUUUUUCAGCUGAUGGGCAGAAGCUGACUCUGCUGGAAUUUUUGGAUUUCCUCCAAGAGGAGCAGAAGGAGAGAGACUGCACCUCUGAGCUUGCUCUGGAACUCAUUGACCGCUAUGAACCUUCAGACAGUGGCAAACUGCGGCAUGUGCUGAGUAUGGAUGGCUUCCUCAGCUACCUCUGCUCUAAGGAUGGAGACAUCUUCAACCCAGCCUGCCUCCCCAUCUAUCAGGAUAUGACUCAACCCCUGAACCACUACUUCAUCUGCUCUUCUCAUAACACCUACCUAGUGGGGGACCAGCUUUGUGGCCAGAGCAGCGUCGAGGGAUAUAUACGGGCCCUGAAGCGGGGGUGCCGCUGCGUGGAGGUGGAUGUAUGGGAUGGACCUAGCGGGGAACCUGUCGUUUACCACGGACACACCCUGACCUCCCGCAUCCUGUUCAAAGAUGUCGUGGCCACAGUAGCACAGUAUGCCUUCCAGACAUCAGACUACCCAGUCAUCUUGUCCCUGGAGACCCACUGCAGCUGGGAGCAGCAGCAGACCAUGGCCCGUCAUCUGACUGAGAUCCUGGGGGAGCAGCUGCUGAGCACCACCUUGGAUGGGGUGCUGCCCACUCAGCUGCCCUCGCCUGAGGAGCUUCGGAGGAAGAUCCUGGUGAAGGGGAAGAAGUUAACACUUGAGGAAGACCUGGAAUAUGAGGAAGAGGAAGCAGAACCUGAGUUGGAAGAGUCAGAAUUGGCGCUGGAGUCCCAGUUUGAGACUGAGCCUGAGCCCCAGGAGCAGAACCUUCAGAAUAAGGACAAAAAGAAGGUUGUGACGUGCCCGCUGUUUUGUCCGUCUAUCUGUUGUCAGAUUGUGGCCCAGGCUCCUAUUUCCAAGCCUGAGUCCCUUCUCUUGUCCCGGCAGGUGAGGCAGGAGGGAGAAUACAGUGGGGAGGCAGUGGGCAGAGGUUUAGGUUGGAUGGCCAUUAUCUUCUUCUCUCUCAGACUGCUGAGGGUUCAAUUCCAUCUUCUUUUCCACCUUCUCCAGAAAUCCAAGCCCAUCUUGUGUCCAGCCCUCUCUUCCCUGGUUAUCUACUUGAAGUCUGUCUCAUUCCGCAGCUUCACACAUUCAAAGGAGCACUACCACUUCUACGAGAUAUCAUCUUUCUCUGAAACCAAGGCCAAGCGCCUCAUCAAGGAGGCUGGCAAUGAGUUUGUGCAGCACAAUACUUGGCAGUUAAGCCGUGUGUAUCCCAGCGGCCUGAGGACAGACUCUUCCAACUACAACCCCCAGGAACUCUGGAAUGCAGGCUGCCAGAUGGUGGCCAUGAAUAUGCAGACUGCAGGGCUUGAAAUGGACAUCUGUGAUGGGCAUUUCCGCCAGAAUGGCGGCUGUGGCUAUGUGCUGAAGCCAGACUUCCUGCGUGAUAUCCAGAGUUCUUUCCACCCUGAGAAGCCCAUCAGCCCUUUCAAAGCCCAGACUCUCUUAAUCCAGGUGAUCAGCGGUCAGCAACUCCCCAAAGUGGACAAGACCAAAGAGGGGUCCAUUGUGGAUCCACUGGUGAAAGUGCAGAUCUUUGGCGUUCGUCUAGACACAGCACGGCAGGAGACCAACUAUGUGGAGAACAAUGGUUUUAAUCCAUACUGGGGGCAGACACUAUGUUUCCGGGUGCUGGUGCCUGAACUUGCCAUGCUGCGUUUUGUGGUAAUGGAUUAUGACUGGAAAUCCCGAAAUGACUUUAUUGGUCAGUACACCCUGCCUUGGACCUGCAUGCAACAAGGUGAGCCAGCCCCUUUGGCCCCUGGCCAAUACCCCAGCUCUGGCUGCCUUCCUAAUGCUGUCCUCCUGCCCCUUCCAGGUUACCGCCACAUUCACCUGCUGUCCAAAGAUGGCAUCAGCCUCCGCCCAGCUUCCAUCUUUGUGUAUAUCUGCAUCCAGGAAGGCCUGGAGGGGGAUGAGUCCUGAGGUGGGCAUUUCACGGGAAGGGUUGGUGUGCUGGCUUUAGACGGGGAGAAACAUCUGGAAGGAUGCUCGAGAGAACAAAUGGAGGUGGUGAAAAUCAAGCUUUGGAUUGUGCAUUCCUAGGCACAAAAUUACCUCAUUCUUCCUAACAAGCAAUCUGGGACCUGAUUUUCCACCUUUUUUCUCUUUUCUUCCCUUCCUUUGUUUUCAUAAGCCUUUGGUAUCUUUCCUGCCCUUUUCCUUUGUGUACUCUAUACUGGAGUUCCCUUCUUCCUCUUGCUGUAGGCUCAAUCCCAUACCGACAUCUACAACUAAUCUUUCCCAUCAACUCUGUGUGAAGGCAGGUUGCAACUAGAAAUUCAGAGGGGCUUGGAAUAGAGAAACCUAAAGAAGCAUCAUCCCCUCCAUCCCCAACUUCCUCAAAGCCCAAAGCCAAGGGAAGGAUAAAUCAAGGCUCAAGGCUUCCCCAGCAAAGAUUAGGGAAAGAGACUUGACCCCAGGACUGUACUACGACUCUUAAGAGAACACUGCACAGCACUCAAAGUCCCCCACUGGACUGCUUCCUCCUUAGCCCCACUGGUAUAAAUACAUCUCUCUCCAA